CGGGCCUCUGUGGGCGGGGCCCGGGCACCAGGGGGCUGCAUGCUCGGGGCUCCAGAGUGGAGCCGGGACGCCCGCCCUGAACCCUGGCCCCUCCGCCCAUCCCUGUCUUGGCUCUCUUUGUCCCCUCCGCCCCACCUAUCUUCUCUCUGAGGGGGUCCCGUUCUCUCUGCGUCUCUUUGUCUCUGUCUCCCUCUGUCUCCGUGUCCCUCUCUCUCUGGGUCUCUGUCCCCCUCUCUCUCUGGGUCUCUGUCCCCCUCUCUCUCUGGGUCUCUGUCCCCCUCUCUCUCUGGGUCUCUGUCCCCCUCUCUCUCUGGGUCUCUGUCCCCCUCUCUCUCUGGGUCUCUGUCCCCCUCUCUCUCUGGGUCUCUGUCCCCCUCUCUCUCUGGGUCUCUGUCCCCCUCUCUCUCUGGGUCUCUGUCCCCGUCUCUCCGGGUCUCUGUUUCCCCUUUUCUGUGGGUCACUGUCCUCAUCUCUUUGGGUCUGUGUUUCCGCUUUUCUCUGUGUCUCUGUCCCCGUCUCUCUGGGUCUCUGUCUCUGUCUCUCUGGGUCUCUGUCUCUGUCUCUCUGGGCCUCUGUUUCCCCUUUUCUCUGUGUCUCUGUCCCCGUCUCUCUGGGUCUCUGUCUUCCUCUCUCUGGGUCUGUUUCCCCCUCUCUCUGGGUCUCUGUCCCCAUCUCUCUGGGUCUCUGUCUGUUUCUCCGGGUCUCCGUCCCUGUCUCUCCGGGUCUCUGUUUCCCCUUUUCUCUGGGUCUCUGUCCUUGUCUCUCUGGGUCUCUGUCCCUGUUUCUCCGGGUCUCUGUCCCCGUCUCUCCGGGUCUCUGUUUCCCCUUUACUCUGGGUUUCUGUCCCCAUCUCUCUGGGUCUCUGUCCCUCUCUCUCUGGGUCUCUGUCCCUCUCUCUCUGGGUCUCUGUCCCUCUCUCUCUGGGUCUCUGUCGCCAUCUCUCUGGGUCUCUGUCCCAUGUCUCUGGGUCUCUGUCCCUCUCUCUCUGGGUCUCUGUCCCUCUCUCUCUGGGUCUCUGUCCCUCUCUCUCUGGGUCUCUGUCCCUCUCUCUCUGGGUCUCUGUCCCCGUCUCUCCGGGUCUCUGUUUCCCCUUUACUCUGGGUUUCUGUCCCCAUCUCUCUGGGUCUCUGUCCCUCUCUCUCUGGGUCUCUGUCCCCGUCUCUCCGGGUCUCUGUUUCCCCUUUACUCUGGGUUUCUGUCCCCAUCUCUCUGGGUCUCUGUCCCUCUCUCUCUGGGUCUCUGUCGCCAUCUCUCUGGGUCUCUGUCCCUCUCUCUCUGGGUCUCUGUCCCUCUCUCUCUGGGUCUUUGUCCCCGUCUCUCUGGGUCUCUGUCCCCGUCUCUCUGGGUCUCUGUCCCUCUCUCUCUGGGUCUCUGUCCCAUCUCUCUGGGUCUCUGUCCCAUGUCUCUGGGUCUCUGUCCCUCUCUCUCUGGGUCUCUGUCCCAUGUCUCUGGGUCUCUGUCCCUCUCUCUCUGGGUCUCUGUCCCCAUCUCUCUGGGUCUCUGUCCCUCUCUCUCUGGGUCUCUGUCCCUCUCUCUCUGGGUCUCUGUCCCCAUCUCUCUGGGUCUCUGUCCCUCUCUCUCUGGGUCUCUGUCCCCGUCUCUCUGGGUCUCUGUCCCCGUCUCUCUGGGUCUCUGUCCCCGUCUCUCUGGGUCUCUGUCCCCCUCCCUGUGUGCCCCGCUCCCAUGUGUCCACAGUUCCUCCGGCUCUCUGACCGAACGGAUCCAGCUGCAGUUUAUAGUCUGGUCACACGCACAUGGGGCUUCCGUGCCCCGAACCUGGUGGUGUCAGUGCUGGGGGGAUCGGGGGGCCCCGUCCUCCAGACCUGGCUGCAGGACCUGCUGCGUCGUGGGCUGGUGCGGGCUGCCCAGAGCACAGGAGCCUGGAUUGUCACUGGGGGUCUGCACACGGGCAUCGGCCGGCAUGUUGGUGUGGCUGUACGGGACCAUCAGAUGGCCAGCACUGGGGGCACCAAGGUGGUGGCCAUGGGUGUGGCCCCCUGGGGUGUGGUCCGGAAUAGAGACACCCUCAUCAACCCCAAGGGCUCGUUCCCUGCGAGGUACCGGUGGCGCGGUGACCCGGAGGACGGGGUCCAGUUUCCCCUGGACUACAACUACUCGGCCUUCUUCCUGGUGGACGACGGCACACACGGCUGCCUGGGGGGCGAGAACCGCUUCCGCUUGCGCCUGGAGUCCUACAUCUCACAGCAGAAGACGGGCGUGGGAGGGACUGGAAUUGACAUCCCUGUCCUGCUCCUCCUGAUUGAUGGUGAUGAGAAGAUGUUGACGCGAAUAGAGAACGCCACCCAGGCUCAGCUCCCAUGUCUCCUCGUGGCUGGCUCAGGGGGAGCUGCGGACUGCCUGGCGGAGACCCUGGAAGACACUCUGGCCCCAGGGAGUGGGGGAGCCAGGCAAGGCGAAGCCCGAGAUCGAAUCAGGCGUUUCUUUCCCAAAGGGGACCUUGAGGUCCUGCAGGCCCAGGUGGAGAGGAUUAUGACCCGGAAGGAGCUCCUGACAGUCUAUUCUUCUGAGGAUGGGUCUGAGGAAUUCGAGACCAUAGUUUUGAAGGCCCUUGUGAAGGCCUGUGGGAGCUCGGAGGCCUCAGCCUACCUGGAUGAGCUGCGUUUGGCUGUGGCUUGGAACCGCGUGGACAUUGCCCAGAGUGAACUCUUUCGGGGGGACAUCCAAUGGCGGUCCUUCCAUCUCGAAGCUUCCCUCAUGGACGCCCUGCUGAAUGACCGGCCUGAGUUCGUGCGCUUGCUCAUUUCCCACGGCCUCAGCCUGGGCCACUUCCUGACCCCGAUGCGCCUGGCCCAACUCUACAGCGCGGCGCCCUCCAACUCGCUCAUCCGCAACCUUUUGGACCAGGCGUCCCACAGCGCAGGCACCAAAGCCCCAGCCCUAAAAGGGGGAGCUGCGGAGCUCCGGCCCCCUGACGUGGGGCAUGUGCUGAGGAUGCUGCUGGGGAAGAUGUGCGCGCCGAGGUACCCCUCCGGGGGCGCCUGGGACCCUCACCCAGGCCAGGGCUUCGGGGAGAGCAUGUAUCUGCUCUCGGACAAGGCCACCUCGCCGCUCUCGCUGGAUGCUGGCCUCGGGCAGGCCCCCUGGAGCGACCUGCUUCUUUGGGCACUGUUGCUGAACAGGGCACAGAUGGCCAUGUACUUCUGGGAGAUGGGUUCCAAUGCAGUUUCCUCAGCUCUUGGGGCCUGUUUGCUGCUCCGGGUGAUGGCACGCCUGGAGCCUGACGCUGAGGAGGCAGCACGGAGGAAAGACCUGGCGUUCAAGUUUGAGGGGAUGGGCGUUGACCUCUUUGGCGAGUGCUAUCGCAGCAGUGAGGUGAGGGCUGCCCGCCUCCUCCUCCGUCGCUGCCCGCUCUGGGGGGAUGCCACUUGCCUCCAGCUGGCCAUGCAAGCUGACGCCCGUGCCUUCUUUGCCCAGGAUGGGGUACAGUCUCUGCUGACACAGAAGUGGUGGGGAGAUAUGGCCAGCACUACACCCAUCUGGGCCCUGGUUCUCGCCUUCUUUUGCCCUCCACUCAUCUACACCCGCCUCAUCACCUUCAGGAAAUCAGAAGAGGAGCCCACACGGGAGGAGCUAGAGUUUGACAUGGAUAGUGUCAUUAAUGGGGAAGGGCCUGUCGGGACGGCGGACCCAGCCGAGAAGACGCCGCUGGGGGUCCCGCGCCAGUCGGGCCGUCCGGGUUGCUGCGGGGGCCGCUGCGGGGGGCGCCGGUGCCUACGCCGCUGGUUCCACUUCUGGGGCGCGCCGGUGACCAUCUUCAUGGGCAACGUGGUCAGCUACCUGCUGUUCCUGCUGCUUUUCUCGCGGGUGCUGCUCGUGGAUUUCCAGCCGGCGCCGCCCGGCUCCCUGGAGCUGCUGCUCUAUUUCUGGGCUUUCACGCUGCUGUGCGAGGAACUGCGCCAGGGCCUGAGCGGAGGCGGGGGCAGCCUCGCCAGCGGGGGCCCCGGGCCUGGCCAUGCCUCACUGAGCCAGCGCCUGCGCCUCUACCUCGCCGACAGCUGGAACCAGUGCGACCUAGUGGCUCUCACCUGCUUCCUCCUGGGCGUGGGCUGCCGGCUGACCCCGGGUUUGUACCACCUGGGCCGCACUGUCCUCUGCAUCGACUUCAUGGUUUUCACGGUGCGGCUGCUUCACAUCUUCACGGUCAACAAACAGCUGGGGCCCAAGAUCGUCAUCGUGAGCAAGAUGAUGAAGGACGUGUUCUUCUUCCUCUUCUUCCUCGGCGUGUGGCUGGUAGCCUAUGGCGUGGCCACGGAGGGGCUCCUGAGGCCACGGGACAGUGACUUCCCAAGUAUCCUGCGCCGCGUCUUCUACCGUCCCUACCUGCAGAUCUUCGGGCAGAUUCCCCAGGAGGACAUGGACGUGGCCCUCAUGGAGCACAGCAACUGCUCGUCGGAGCCCGGCUUCUGGGCACACCCUCCUGGGGCCCAGGCGGGCACCUGCGUCUCCCAGUAUGCCAACUGGCUGGUGGUGCUGCUCCUCGUCAUCUUCCUGCUCGUGGCCAACAUCCUGCUGGUCAACUUGCUCAUUGCCAUGUUCAGUUACACAUUCGGCAAAGUACAGGGCAACAGCGAUCUCUACUGGAAGGCGCAGCGUUACCGCCUCAUCCGGGAAUUCCACUCUCGGCCCGCGCUGGCCCCGCCCUUUAUCGUCAUCUCCCACUUGCGCCUCCUGCUCAGGCAAUUGUGCAGGCGACCCCGGAGCCCCCAGCCGUCCUCCCCGGCCCUCGAGCAUUUCCGGGUUUACCUUUCUAAGGAAGCCGAGCGGAAGCUGCUAACGUGGGAAUCGGUGCAUAAGGAGAACUUUCUGCUGGCACGCGCUAGGGACAAGCGGGAGAGCGACUCCGAGCGUCUGAAGCGCACGUCCCAGAAGGUGGACUUGGCACUGAAACAGCUGGGACACAUCCGCGAGUACGAACAGCGCCUGAAAGUGCUGGAGCGGGAGGUCCAGCAGUGUAGCCGCGUCCUGGGGUGGGUGGCCGAGGCCCUGAGCCGCUCUGCCUUGCUGCCCCCAGGUGGGCCGCCACCCCCUGACCUGCCUGGGUCCAAAGACUGAGCCCUGCUGGCGGACUUCAAGGAGAAGCCCCCACAGGGGAUUUUGCUCCUAGAGUAAGGCUCAUCUGGGCCUCGGCCCCCGCACCUGGUGGCCUUGUCCUUGAGGUGAGCCCCAUGUCCAUCUGGGCCACUGUCAGGACCACCUUUGGGAGUGUCAUCCUUACAAACCACAGCAUGCCCGGCUCCUCCCAGAACCAGUCCCAGCCUGGGAGGAUCAAGGCCUGGAUCCCGGGCCGUUAUCCAUCUGGAGGCUGCAGGGUCCUUGGGGUAACAGGGACCACAGACCCCUCACCACUCACAGAUUCCUCACACUGGGGAAAUAAAGCCAUUUCAGAGGAA